GUUGUUGGGCUCCUCUGAGCGGUUGAGGUUGGGGCUGGGGUUGAGCUCGGGUUGGGUUCCUCCUGGGGCAGGAGGGAAAGGCGGGAGCCAGGGCGUCAGGGCCUGCGGACGAUGUGUGUGUGAAAGGGCGCGUCAGCCAUAAGAAGCCAUAUGCGUGCGAGCCGGUCCCCACCGUCCCCGCGGCGUUGUCACCAUCAUCAUGAGGCCACUGGAGCAGCCUCAGGCGCUGCUGCCGGGGGGCCGGGCGCGGGGUGCGUCGGGCUCUGCAGGUUGGCACUCACACCCAGCGCGCAGGAUGGCAGGAAUAGCACAUUUCAAACCUACAAGAAAGAAGUGUGCCUCCCCCGUCAUUCGAUGCACCCUGGCCCCUGGGCCAUCUGCUGUGAAUGCCAGACCAGAUUCGGGGGCCGCCUGCCUGUGUCCAGGGUGGAAGCAGCACUGCCUUACUGGGUCCCUCUGUCCCUGAGACCCCGAAAGCAGAGUCAAAAGACGGUUCAAUUUCCUAUCCCCCAAACCGCCAAGAUGUGCCCCUGCCUAUGCCACCGCUUUGGGGGCCGCCUCCCGAUGCCUAGGGACCAGGCAGUGAUGCCCUACUGGGUGCCCCAGGUCCUGAGGUCUCAGCAGCAGAUAGUCAGGAGGCAGCAGAGUUUGAAAGGCAUCCAAGCACCCCUGCUGGAUGCAUGCUGCUGGCACAACUGCUGGCGGAUCUGCGGUGAUGAGUGCCUGUUGUCCAAGUUCCAGCAGCUCCAGGCCCCCUACCAGGACCAGCUACCGGCUCCUGCAGCGCGUCUGCUGCCCCUCGGCCUCCUGACCCUCCUCCAGGCCAUCCCGAGGGUCAUCAUGGCCAUUCGCCAGUGUUUUGGGGUUUGAAGUUGGAAUCUUCAGCUACUGUCAAGAACAGCCACAAAAAUGUGUCACGAUCAAGAUCUUUGAGAGUCCACCAAUCAGGAGGCGUCUGUGACAGUCGCUGUCUUCUCAGAACAGAAUCCACACCCAGGAUUCAACCCAAAUGAUUUCUCAUCAGGUGAUUCUUGGUUGUAGCAAAGUUCAUGUGAAUGUGGGUGAGUUUCUGUUAUGAAUGUGGUCAAUAAAUGUUAUUUGUGAAACUCUAAA